GCCUAGCGACAGCAGGGACGCUCGUGGGACCCCAGGCUAAACCCCGCUGUAGCCUUAAAUCUCCUACCAUGGAGGAAGAAGGCGGCGGCCGCAGCUGUGGGACCACUAGGGAGCUGCAGAAGCUGAAGCAGCAGGCGAUGGAGUACUACCGGGAGAACGACGUUCCGCGCAGGCUGGAAGAGCUGCUCAACUCCACCUUCUACCUCCAGCCUGCCGACGUCUACGGGCACCUGGCAAACUGCUUUUCUAAACUUGCAAAGCCUCCCACCAUAUGCAAAAUAGUGGGGAAAGACGUACUAGAUGGACUGGGGCUUCCAACCCUGCAAGUGGACAUAUUCUGCACCAUUCAAAACUUUCCCAAGAACGUAUGUUCUGUGGUGAUCUCGACUCAUUUUGAAGUCCAUGAGAAUGCUCUGCCCGAGCUGGCCAAGGCGGAGGAGGCAGAGAGGGCCAGCGCGGUGAGCACCGCCGUGCAGUGGGUCAACAGCACCAUCACGCACGAGCUCCAGGGGAUGGCACCCUCUGACCAGGCAGAGGUGGAUCACCUACUCAGGAUAUUCUUCGCAAGUAAAGUACAAGAAGAUAAGGGGAGAAAAGAAUUGGAAAAGAGCCUGGAAUACUCAACAGUGCCUACACCUCUACCUCCAGUACCACCACCACCACCCCCUCCACCUCCUACCAAAAAAAAGGGGCAAAAGCCAGGGAGGAAGGAUACUAUUACAGAGAAACCUAUUGCGCCUGCAGAGCCUGUUGAGCCUGUACUCAGUGGCAGUAUGGCCAUAGGGGCCGUGUCACUAGCUGUUGCCAAAGCCUGUGCCAUGCUGCUUAAUAAACCUCUGUACUUAAAUAUCGCUCUACUGAAGCACAAUCAGGAACAGCCAACAACGCUAUCUAUGCCUUUGCUGAUGGUAUCGCUGGUCAGCUGUGGGAAGUCAUCAUCUGGGAAGCUAAAUUUAAUGAAAGAAGUGAUUUGUAUACCCCAUCCUGAAUUAACAACCAAACAAGGUGUCGAGAUGCUUAUGGAAAUGCAGAAACAUAUCAACAAAAUAAUUGAAAUGCCCUCUCCUCCAAAAGCAGAGACAAAAAAAGGGCACGAUGGAAGCAAAAGAGGUCAACAGCAGAUCACUGGCAAGAUGUCUCAUCUUGGCUGUUUAACCAUUAACUGUGACUCCAUAGAACAGCCACUGCUUCUAAUACAGGAAAUCUGUGCCAACCUGGGGCUAGAACUGGGAACAAAUCUGCAUCUAGCUAUCAACUGUGCUGGACAUGAGCUGAUGGACUACAAUAAAGGAAAGUAUGAAGUGAUCAUGGGCACAUACAAAAAUGCAGCGGAGAUGGUUGACCUGUAUGUGGAUCUGAUCAACAAGUACCCUUCAAUUAUUGCCUUAAUUGAUCCUUUCAGGAAGGAGGACUCUGAACAGUGGGACAGCAUCUAUCACGCACUUGGUUCCAGGUGUUACAUAAUUGCAGGAACUGCUUCCAAAAGCAUUUCUAAACUUCUAGAGCAAGGAAACAUCAGCAUCCCCAAAUCCAAUGGGCUGAUCAUAAAACACACAAACCAAACUACAAUGUCUGACUUGGUGGAAAUAACCAAUCUGAUUGACAGUAAGAAGCACAUCACUGUCUUUGGAAGUACAGAAGGAGAAUCAUCUGAUGACAGCCUUGUCGAUUUGGCUGUUGGGCUUGGUGUCCGGUUCAUCAAGUUGGGGGGUCUUUCCCGUGGUGAACGAGUGACUAAAUACAACCGCCUUCUCACUAUAGAGGAAGAACUUGUCCAGAAUGGAACACUGGGUUUCAAAGAAGAACACACUUUUUUUUACUUUAAUGAGGAAGCUGAAAAGGCUGCGGAGGCACUUGAGGCUGCUGCGGCUAGGGAGCCGCUGGUGCCCACCUUCCCCACACAAGGUGUAGAGGAAUCAGCCGAAACAGGAGCAUCCUCUGGAUAGGGCUGUACACACCCCAGGUUCCAGCCACACCAUCAGUAUUAGUAGACCGGGAGGUCUGAAGUACGGCGCCGUGUCUCCACAUGGAGUUUCCUCUUCAACUUCACCAACUCUUGUGGUUUUUAUUCUUCUAAUUCCACUGUUUGGUAAAUUACAUAUAUGAUGUUUUUGCCUGAAAUUCUGUGAACUUCGUUUUGCAGCCACCACACUUCCAUGUGGAUUUUGUUUGUCUAUUAGCUCUCCUGUCCAUUUUUCAGGGACACGCUCCAGUAAAAGAGGCCAAUAUUUUUGUUGCCAACUCCACACUCAGUCAAACACCCCAUCCUUUACCAAUCAGAAUAUCUCUGAGAACAAAAACCUAAUGACCCUAGAAGCUCUCUGUGCUGGGAACAGAUGUCCAUCUUCUGUGUUUAUUCUACAUGUCUGUGCUGAAAAGCACUGACACAUUUUUGUAACCAACCUCACGUAGAAGUGUGAGAGCAUCACCAUUUUUUGUAAGAGCCAAUUUCAUCUCACUUUCCUACCCUUGAUUCCUUUUUUCCUAAUUCCCUCUCCUUUUUAAAUUUUAGUUUUUCUUGUAUUAUUUUUAUCUUUGCGAGUCUUCUUAGAUCCUUUUUGGAGUAAGAAUGAGUAUAAAUGAAUAAGCACAUCAGUAAAUGAAUUAAUAUUCUCAAGGUUAUUAAAUGCCCAGUUAUUCAUACCACAGCAUUUAAAAAGCAAUCCGCAAGUGAUAAAAAAAAAAAAAAAAAAUGAUGUGACAUAUCCAUUGCCUGAAUUGCUCUUUUGUAAGCCAGUGUUGGGAUUAUAGCAGAGGAGUAGCAGAAAUAAAUAUAUUCAGACACAAACAUAUAGAUAUAAUAAUAUCCAACCACUUUAUAUGAUUUAGGGUCUCGUUAAAAUGGUUACCAUUUGCUUCUCCUAAAAAUUAUAUAAAU